GAACCCGGAAGCGAGGGACCCACGUGGGAGCCUGGGAGCGGGUGGUCGUAGCUCGGUAGUCCAGUUGUGGGUAAUCGGGGCUGUUUGUUCCUGUCCGAGAGAGCUCGGCGGAGACGGCUGUCGAGUACCCUUCACCUCGGUGUUGGGAGCCUGGGAGCGAACUGCGGCGCGGGUUACCGCUCCCGGGGACGCAGCAAGGGGCAUCGAGUCCCUGGCGGGAGCUGCGCCAUGGCAUUGCUCUCGACCGUCCGGGGCGCGACCUGGGGUCGCCUCGUCACCCGUCAUUUCUCCCAUGCAGCGCGGCAUGGGGAGCGGCCUGGUGGGGAGGAGCUAAGCCGCUUGCUGCUGGAUGACCUGGUGCCGACCUCUCGGCUGGAGCUUCUGUUUGGCAUGACCCCGUGUCUCCUGGCUCUGCAGGCCGCCCGCCGCUCUGUGGCCCGGCUCCUGCUCCAGGCGGGUAAAGCUGGGCUGCAGGGGAAGCGGGCCGAGCUGCUCCGGAUGGCCGAGGCGCGGGACAUUCCAGUUCUGCGGCCCAGACGGCAGAAACUGGACACAAUGUGCCGCUACCAGGUCCACCAGGGUGUCUGCAUGGAGGUGAGCCCGCUGCGGCCCCGGCCUUGGAGAGAGGCCGGGGAGGCGAGCCCAGGCGACGACCCCCAGCAGUUGUGGCUCGUCCUCGAUGGGAUCCAGGAUCCCCGGAAUUUUGGGGCUGUGCUGCGUUCCGCACACUUCCUCGGAGUGGAUAAGGUCAUCACCAGCCGGAGAAACAGCUGCCCGCUCACUCCAGUAGUCAGCAAGUCCAGCGCGGGGGCUAUGGAGGUGAUGGACGUGUUCUCCACUGAUGACCUCACCGGAUUUUUACAGACCAAAGCCCAGCAGGGCUGGCUCGUGGCCGGCACGGUGGGCUGCCCAAGCACAGAGGAUCCCCAGUCCUCCGAGAUCCCCAUCAUGAGUUGCUUGGAGUUCCUCUGGGAACGGCCUACUCUCCUUGUGCUGGGGAAUGAGGGCUCAGGUCUAUCCCAGGAGGUGCAGGCCUCCUGCCAGCUUCUCCUCACCAUCCUGCCCCGGCGCCAGCUGCCUCCUGGACUUGAGUCCUUGAACGUCUCUGUGGCUGCAGAGUUGGGAACCUUGAAUGAGAUCACACACACAAAGGCACUCAGCACACCAAACGCGGGGCAUCCCUCCUGUCCUGCCAGUUUGCAGGCCGUCUGAGCUCAGCUCAUUGAUUGAUUGAUUGGGUGAAAGGAUCAUGGAGAGGAUGCCAUCCAGUUGGAGAUAUGGUGUGAGCUGAAAAUCCCAGAGUAAAUGUCCUUUCCAGGACAGCAGAGACGAAAAGAGCUUUUCUGGCUGGGAGAUUCCAAGAAGGCUUUGUGAAGAAGGAGCAGCAUUAACCCGAGUUUCUCAGUGGGCUCAGACUUACAGGUGGAGAAGGGAAGGGGAUGCGGUGGGAGGAAUGGCAUGGGCAAAGGCCUUCAGUGAGAAAGCUGGGCACACAGCCGUAAAAUGGCUGUGAAUAGGCUGCUUUCCUAGAGCAAAGGGUAAGUGCGGUAAAACGGAAAGGGCGUUGUUCCCAAUUCCUGGAUUAUUAAAACAAAAGCGGGAUAUAUUGGGAAAAGAGUAGGAGGCUGAAUUAUUUGGAUAAUUACAAAACUGUUCCCUUGAAUCCCCGAUUUGCUUUGCUCCCUGUGGGUGGCUUGCCUCCUUUCUCCUUCACCGCGGGGAUCACAGGCUUCAGAAACCCUGAGGGGAAUGUCCCCAGAGAAGAGCCCCUCCCGUCUCCCCUUCUCCCUCAGGUCGUCACUUUGCCUCCUUAACCCCACUCCCACUCCUCAAAGGAAGAAGGUGGUGUUGGAGGAAGACUGGAGGGGGAGCCCCCUAUCUGAGGUCCCCAGACUGUCUUCAGAGAAAGGGAGGAGCAGCCUCAGCUUGGCGUCUGGGGCCCUGUUUCAUCCUUGGGUCCGUGAGGGAAGAGGAUUCUGCUCCCUGCCAGAAACAUUCCUGUAGAGUAUUUGCAUUACAUCCGGCUCACACCCUCUUCCUUCGAAGAACAGAUACCAGGAGAUGGUGUUUGGGCAGGGGGAUGGAGGAAGGAGGGAGAGAGGAGAGGGAGGAGGGGACGAAGAGGAAGAGGAAGAAGACGACAAAGAGGAGAAGAGGAGGAGGAAGAGGAAGAAGAGAAGGGGAGGAGGAAGAGGAGGAAAGAGCAGGAAAAGGAGGAGGAGGAGGAAGGGGAGAAGGAGGAGGGGAGGAGAGGGAGGAGGCGUAGGCAGCCAGCUGUCAGAGCUGCUUAUUUUAUUUUUCUUGCUCCUGGAGCAGGCUGGCAGAGCAGUCCCCGAUAGCAGCAGGAAUGAAGAACAUGGGCCGAAGGAGGAGAUAAUUUAGGCCUGUUUCCCUGGCUGAUUCCGCUGUGCCUCCUUCUAUCUCUCUGCCUCUGAUUCUCUCCUCCUCUGUCUCUCUCAUGGUCUCUGAAGGAGAUGAAUUCCAGGUGACUCUCCGGGCUCCACUGUGCUUCCUGGGAGCUGCGCGCUGGGGGUGAUGUUUGUCCCUUCUCACUGUAGACUGAGCUUGGGAUUUCUCAGCCCCCAGUUACUUAGAUGUGGCUUUGGUCCUCUUUGGGGCCCUAGGGUGGGUGGGGAGCCCACAUUUUCUCUCUCCCCCAUUCUUCUAGAGCCCAGCCAGCCUCCAUGGGCCACCAACUACAUCCUCCAUGGAGAAUCUUCAAAGCUCUAGAGCCCCUAUUCCCAAACCAUUUCCUGUCUUUUUUAUUACAUGGACUUACUCCAAAAAGGAGCGAAAGAACUUGUACAUGUUUCCAUUCUGAUCAGUUCUUUCUGGAUUUUCCGGGCAUUUUUGUUACCAGGUGUCUGAAAGAUCCUGAGUGCUAUGAACUGGCUUUCACAUCUGCGACCUGCUGUAGCCCUCCCACAACACUGGGCCCAGGGGUGUUGAUUUUCUUUUACAAAUGGGGCAACUAAGGCAUGUUAACAGCUGAGCCUAGGUUUGAACCUGGUUCCCCCUGUGCUGGUGCAGAGCUGUUUCCCCUGGGAUAUAUGUCUCCAGUGUCACUGCCCUUCCACUGGGUUUCCUGCUUUUACCUAACAUCGACUCACACGGUCAUUUUCGGGGUGGCAGGGCCUCCUGUCUUGUCGUUUUAAUGGCCACAUGGCAUUCCAUCAUGUUGAUGGAUCAUUUUGUUUGGUCACUCCCUCAUCGUUGGAUAUGUGUGAGGUGUCUAAUUUCUUGCUAUAAUAAAUGCAACUGCUGUAUUUUGUUCAAA